GAGGACACAGUGAGAAGAUGGGGGUCUGCUCGCCAGGAAGGAGCCCUCACCAGCAGCCGCAUCGCUCAGCACCUUGAUCCUGGACUUCCAGCCUCCAGAGCUGUGAGAAACAAACCUCUAUCAUCUACCAGCCGCCCACGGCGUGGGAUUUGUGUUACAGCAGCCUGAGCUGACCCAGACGCCAAGGAGCAACACACGCACCAGGAACAGAGGCCCAGAGAGGUGAAGCAAGAGCCCGCAGAUCCCAGCCCCGCUACGUCAGGAAGCCCGGCUGGACCCACGUCUGGCUCCAGGGUCCUGUGUUGGUGAUCACAGCCCUGUGGCUGUUCCCAGCGGUCACAGGCCCUGAGGAGCUUCAGUCCCUGGAACACACACAAGAGGUGUCCUGAGGACACGCAUGGAACUGCGCUUGAGCUGCAAUCUGUCCCCUAGUUCCCGCCUCGCUUGGGCAUCUGACGGCCUUUAUCUCUUCUCCCCUGAUCCUUAUCCGACACCCCAACUCUUCUGCAGACUCCAGUUCCUUCCCAGUGCCCUGGGUCCUUCAGGGUCCUUGGGAUGAGACAUCUCCGAACACGAGCUUUUCUCAGCUGGCGUCUGAGGGUGAUGGCGUUCUGCCCACAGGCAUCCGCCUGCACAGGCCUCCCUGACAAGAGGGGCUGAGGGGGAAAGGAGUGAGACAGAAAACCAGCAGGGCCCCGGGGACCGAGCCCUGGAGAAGCGCCAGUUCCCGCCCAGAUGAGGGCCGACACCUCGGAAGGACCGGCCUGGGGGGUCGCCCUCCCCAGGCCCUCUGCCUCCCAUCGUGGCAUGGACUGCACCUUUGGUGUCCUUCCCUCCCAUGGCCUCUGAGUCCCUGAACACUGGCUCAUACCUGCUCCACCCAGAUACAGCACAGAGGAGAGACCCGGGCAGCCUCUAAGGGCAGUGCCUUGAGGGCCAGUGCCUGGUGCACCUGCCGCACAGGGCACAGGACACAAAGGGCUGGGUGAUCCAUUCAGGCUCUCUCAGGGCCCGCGUCGAGCUCGGCCUGGGUCCCAGGAAGGCUGCCAGGCACCAGGUGCUGCCUGAGUCCGAAGGAGGCCCUGACUCCAGGUCGCCCACGGCAGGAGUGGGCCCCACGGAGCUUCUGUGGACCCUUGACCCGCCACCCUCAGGUGGAAGCCAUCAGGCUGCGCUGGAUAAGCCAGCCUCUCCCCACCUCUGCCAUUCAAGUCGGUGCCAGUGCUGACUGGAGAGAUCCCAGAGAUAACUGUGAAAUGCCUGUCACUGUUCUCAGCUUCGUUUAUGUAGGCUGCAGAGCCAAGACAGCAAAUACUGCACAUCCGGGAGCCUCCCCAAGGCCGGCCCUGGGCCUUCCCCCAGGAAGAGCCCCACGGCCAGCUCCUUCCUGUUCCCCUGGCGGCCCCUCGCUUCUUCCUUCUGGAUGGGGGCCCAGGGGGCCCAGGAGAGUAUAAAGGCGAUGUGGAGGGUGCCCGGCACAACCAGACGCCCAGUCACAGGCGAGAGCCCUGGGAUGCACCGGCCAGAGGCCAUGCUGCUGCUGCUCACGCUUGCCCUCCUGGGGGGCCCCACCUGGGCAGGGAAGAUGUAUGGCCCUGGAGGAGGCAAGUAUUUCAGCACCACUGAAGACUACGACCAUGAAAUCACAGGGCUGCGGGUGUCUGUAGGUCUUCUCCUGGUGAAAAGUGUCCAGGUGAAACUUGGAGACUCCUGGGACGUGAAACUGGGAGCCUUAGGUGGGAAUACCCAGGAAGUCACCCUGCAGCCAGGCGAAUACAUCACAAAAGUCUUUGUCGCCUUCCAAGCUUUCCUCCGGGGUAUGGUCAUGUACACCAGCAAGGACCGCUAUUUCUAUUUUGGGAAGCUUGAUGGCCAGAUCUCCUCUGCCUACCCCAGCCAAGAGGGGCAGGUGCUGGUGGGCAUCUAUGGCCAGUAUCAACUCCUUGGCAUCAAGAGCAUUGGCUUUGAAUGGAAUUAUCCACUAGAGGAGCCGACCACUGAGCCACCAGUUAAUCUCACAUACUCAGCAAACUCACCCGUGGGUCGCUAGGGUGGGGUAUGGGGCCAUCCGAGCUGAGGCCAUCUGGGUGGUGGUGGCUGAUGGUACUGGAGUAACUGAGUCGGGACGCUGAAUCUGAAUCCACCAAUAAAUAAAGGUUCUGCAGAA